AGUUGUCGCUCCGCGCCUGCGCCCGUUGUCUCCCUGCUCGCUCCGGGUCCCGGCGCCGCGCCAUGUGGGCUGCGGCGGGCGGGCUGUGGCGCUCCCGCGCGGGUCUCCGGGCCCUGUUCCGUAGCCGCGAUGCUGCGCUAUUUCCAGGCUGCGAGCGGGGACUUCACUGCUCUGCUGUCUCCUGCAAGAACUGGCUCAAGAAAUUUGCCUCGAAAACCAAAAAAAAGGUUUGGUAUGAAAGUCCUUCCUUGGGUUCUCACUCGACUUACAAACCAUCCAAGUUGGAAUUCCUCAUGAGGAGCACCUCAAAGAAAACCAGGAAGGAAGACCAUGCGCGCCUGAGGGCCCUGAACGGCCUCCUCUAUAAGGCACUGACAGACCUGCUGUGUACCCCUGAAGUGAGUCAGGAGCUGUAUGACCUUAACGUGGAGCUCUCCAAGGUUUCCCUGACUCCAGACUUCUCAGCCUGCCGAGCGUACUGGAAGACAACGCUCUCUGCUGAGCAGAACGCACACAUGGAGGCUGUCCUGCAGAGAAGUGCCGCGCACAUGAGGCACCUUUUGAUGUCCCAGCAGACCCUGAGGAAUGUGCCACCGAUAGUGUUUGUUCAAGACAAGGGAAAUGCAGCUCUAGCUGAGCUUGAUCAGUUACUGGCAGUCGCAGACUUUGGACCCCGGGAUGAAAGAGACAACUUUGUACAAAAUGAUUUCAGGGACCCUGAUGCCCCACAACCCUGCGGCACCACAGAGCCGACCACAAGCUCCAGUCUGUGUGGGAUCGAUCAUGAGGCGCUCAACAAGCAGAUUAUGGAGUACAAAAGGAGGAAAGAUAAAGGGCUCGGGGGCCUGGUGUGGCAGGGGCAGGUGGCUGAGCUGACAACGCAGAUGAAAAAGGGAAGGAAGAGGGCCAAGCCCCGCCUGGAGCAGGACAGCUCCCUCAAGAGUUACCUGUCAGGCGAGGAGGUUGAAGAUGACCUGGACCUGGUUGGUGCCCCGGAGUACGAAUGCUAUGCCCCGGACACAGAGGAGUUGGAGGCAGAGAGAGGAGGUGGCAGAACAGAGGAUGGCCACAGCUGCGGAGCAAGCAGGGAGUAGAUGGAGAGGCUCUGCCCAUCCCACAUUUGCAGGGAAAAGCAUUGGCACGCAACGCAGCAUGUGGCUUCAUUGAGGCAGUUGAUGGAGUUAAACCAUCUGCUCUUCUGCUACUUCAACAUUUUCUAGCUUUUCCGUGUAUCUAAACACAAUUUGCUACACAAGUCACUGUUUUUUUUUCCAUGCACUGUGUGUAAUUUAAAAAUUAAAUGGCCAUCUUAUCACAGAUUCUCACAAAAAGAAAAUGGUAAAAUAGUGUCUCUGAGAUGCUGGCAUGGCCACCUCCACCUGCAGAGCCCUGCCAGGUGCCAGUGAGUGCUUGGCCCGAGGGGUCAGGCCACAGCAGUGGCCGGGGUAAGAACUGAACCUGCAAACCUGGGGAGAACAGAGGGUCCCCAGAGCCUCCCAACCCCCUGGAGCUGGGCUCCGUCCCUGGGGCUGCUGGGCUGGCACGUGGCGCCGGGGGCUCCAUCCCUGGGGCUGCUGGGUCGGCACGUGGCGCCGGGGGCUCCGUCCCUGACUGGCCUCUUCACAGCUUUGUGCAGCAGGCUCCACCUUCUGGUUCAGGCCAAGGUUGGGCAGAAAGUGAGUUGGGUUUGCUGGGGCUUCCUGGGCGACCCCGGCUCUGACCGUGGUUCCAUCACGCCUGAAGUAGUAACACUUUUCCCUUGGUGCCCGUGGCCAGCUAGUGUAUUUUCUAAUCCAUCCAAAGGUGAAACAGACUUGGUCUUUGCCUUCUGAAGAGUGUGCGACUCUGAGUCAUACUGAAUUCUUUGUGUCACCUCCGACGCAAAGAUUCGUUUUGCUGUUUAUCAGAAGAGAAAACACAGAUUCCAUACCUUGUCAGCUCCUAUUUAGUUCGGCUUCCCUCUUAAUGUCCCAGCCCCUGUGAGCUGUCAGGUUCUAAAUUCAGAAUUCUCUCAAUUCUGUCAGGUUCUGCACUACGAGUCAGUGUCAUCCCUCCAAGCCCUGGCUCUCUGCCAGUGCAGCAGGGCUGUGAGAAUCAAGACGGCACAGGGAAGGCAUCUGUCCCAGCAUUUGCACAUGACAGGUGCCCACGGUGCAGGAGUAGAAUCUGUGGAAGCAGCAGUGGCUUUAGUUGCUGUGCCCUGCCACCUCCUCCCCAAAAAGGAGAAGUGUCCAAGGGAUAGCAGACCCGUAGCACUGAGCGGCCUGCCGUGCUGACCACUGGAUCCAGGCCACGUGCUGCAGACAGCGGCUGUGGGCGAGUGAUGAGGCCACUACCCAGAAAGCUGCAUGUGCACUGUGUGGGGUAAGGACAGUAGGAGAUGCUGCUGCAAGAUGCUGACUCCCUUGUUUUUCUUUUCAUUUGUGCUCUGGGACUAAGCUGUGUAUAAGUCAUCAAAUGGCAGAAGCAAGAUUUUUCUUUUGAGAUCUAGGAAAUUAUUUGUUUAUACUCUACACUCUUAUUUCCUAUAUCAGGAUGGGGAGGCCACUACCUCAGGCCAGUUAAACUAAGAAGAAAGAAUUUAAGGCAAUUUGUAAGGAUAGACAAAACCCCACAUGAUGGUAUGAGUAGGAGAGAGAAAAAAAAAAGGGAGCCAGAAAUUAGGUUACAAAGUGUACACCACACAUAAAGGCUGAUGCCUCUGUUACACCGUGAGCCAAAUGUUUAUCUCUAGGGUUUCUGGUAGCCAGUUGCGGGGUGUCCAGUGAAGGGGUGUACAUGUCUGUGGUUAAUCAUAUAGGUCAGGAUAAUGAGGUGAUACUGCAGUGACAAAUGGCAAAUCUCCCUGGCUUACAACAACCAGUUUGCCUCUUAUUCUUCUAGGGGACCAUCAUGGGCUGAGGUCAGGCCAAGGCCUUUUGUAUCUGGUGUUACUGGAACAUGGCUAUGUGAAUUCAUUUAUGUACAAGAGACCUCCCCAUCCUGAUGUAGGAAAUGAAUGGUGAUGAUUUACGAGCGCAACAUCCUAAAAAACGUUUUUGUAUUUCCCUAGCAAGAUAACUUCAGGUUACAAGGCUCUGGUACUUGACCAUGAUGACUCCAUGAGAAAACAGCAGAACGCCAGCUUUGCAGGUACCUCCACAGCACUGCCGGGCUGGGAACAGGGCCAGUGCUUGCACCAGCGCUGGAGGGGGCCACAGCAGAGUAAAGACAGAGUCUGCCAUGCAGGAGUGCUUCGCAGGUCAGGCACUGCUCUGAGUGCUUUGUGUUAACCUGCCCCCCGCCCCCUAACUUGGGAAAGGUGUUAAAGAAGGAGAGAACGCCCUCAAUGGUGUGUCCUUUGCAUACACACCUUUGCAUGCAUCUGAUGUGCCCAGGCUGUGUUUUAUUGUUCUAGCAAUUUAUUGUUACAAAACAGAUUGCUGCCAUCAAUUUGUCUCAGGUCCUUCUAGCACAUCUGACAGGGACUAGUGUCUAGAGCCAUGAGGACAGAGACCAGAAGGGACAAGAAGGAGUGGGCAGAGGGAAUGGAAGGUAGAGUUAGGCCCAGAGAGCCCCAGGCUGCUGCCCAGACCUCCACGCCUGUGCCGGAUGUGGUGUUGGCAUCCAUAGCAGUCUCGCAAAGUUGUUCUCAUUUUCCAAAUAAGGAAUCUGAGGCCCAGGGAGAGGUGAAGUGCUGCAGGAGAUCCAACCAGGCGCCGGCUCAGUGCCUCCUAGAAAGAGGAGUGUGGGCACGUUUGCAGGGGAUCCAACCAGGCGUCAGCUCAGUGCCUCCUAGAAAGUGGAGUGUGGGCAUGUUUGCAGGGGAUCCAACCAGGCGUCGGCUCAGUGCCUCCUAGAAAGUGGAGUGUGGGCACGUUUGCAGGGGAUCCAACCAGGCGUCUGCUCAGUGCCUCCUAGAAAGUGGAGUGUGGGCACGUUUGUAGGGGAUCCCACCAGGCAUCAGCUCAGUGCCUCCUAGAAAGAGGAGUGUGGGCACGUUUCAGAGAAAACUGGCUUAGGCCUCCCUGUUUCUGGCGUGGCCUUCCCUGGGAGCGAGUUAGGGACACGGAAGCUCACCCGCUUCUGAAUGGGUCCACUCCUGGGGAUUUCCGCGGCCUUCCCUGGGAGCGGGUUAGGGACACGGAAGCUCACCCCCUUCUGAAUGGGUCCACUCCUGGGGAUUUCCGCGGCCUUCCCUGGGAGCGGGUUAGGGACAUGGAAGCUCACCCUCUUCUGAAUGGGUCCACUCCUGGGGAUUUCCACGGCCUUUCCUGGGAGCAGGUUAGGGACAUGGAAGCUCACGCCCUUCUGAAUGGGUCCACUCCCGGGGAUUUCCAUGGCCUUCCCUGGAUGAUCCACUCCUGGGGAUUUUCCGCAGCUCUCCAGAUGACGUGCACGCACACUAAACACCCAGAAGUUAGGGAGGCACUGAUCCAGUGAAGUCCUCAGAUCAACCUUGUGAGCUUUUUACAAGUACCUGUCACUGUUAAACUGCUGAUGAAAUGUGAAACGACUUCACAGGUUUUCAGUCUGAUAAGCUCUCCUGUGUCACUGUCCCUUACCUUGUUAGUAAAGGUCAAUGGUUCUCAAAGUUCCGGGCACAUCCCCUGGGGGCUCAUAAAACCAGACUGUCGGCCACUUCAGCCUUCUGGUUCGCUGUUCCUUGGUAAUGCAGAUGGCCCAGUAAGCAACUCUACAAACAUUAGAACAUUUUGAGGUAGACAGGGGAACUUAAUCACCCCUUGUAGGCCCCCAGAAGACUGGACCCAACAUCCAGCACAAUGCCUCUCAGCCUUGGCUGUGCAUCUGAAACACCUGCUGUUUGAAGACACCUGGGCCUGGAGACGGGCCAGAGCCACCUUGGUGGUCUGAGUAUGAGGCCAGCAUUAGAACCUCUGCUCUACGGGUGACUGCCCUGGGUUGAUUUUUUUCCAGUAUUAUCUUUAGUACAGAAUCUUUUCCUCUCUAAGGGCCUGAGACCCUCUCUUAGGAAUAGAAGUACAGUUUUCUUCCCCACUCCUUUUGUCCAGAAGGAAAACCUGGUUUUACAUCAGAAACUUGAGGUACUUUGAAAAUUUGCCAGCUGCCUUGAAGGAGAGAGGGCUUGAGUGUAUUUUGGGGGAAGAAUGAGGGGACAACAGGGCAGGGAGAAGGGACAGAGCUAGAGGAAGGACAGGCCUGUGCCACCCAGGCCAGGGUAAGGGGAGCAGAGACCUUUUGGUUCCUGGUUUGUGACACAGGAAGGGAGGGAACUGGGGAGGACAGGUCAUGAUCAGUGUUUCCUGAUUAAAAAUUUUUUAUUUUUAUUUUUAAUUAUCAUGGGCACAGAGUAGGUGUAUAUAUUUGUGGGGUACAUGAGAUGUUUUGAUACAGACAUGCAAUGUGAAAAAGCACAUCAUGGAGACUGGGGCACCCAUCCCCUCAAGCAUUUAUCCUUUGUGCCACAAACAAUCCGAUUAUAUUGUUUUAGUUAUUUUUAAAUAUGCAAUUAAAUUGUUAUUGACUAUAGUCACCCUUCUGUGCUGCUGCUCUACUGUGGCCUCAAAGAUCAUAAAUGCUGUGGGUGCUGGCAAGAUACUGAAAUAAAUUAAUUCUGUAUUUCUAAAAA